AUGGUCCGCUGCCUGGGGCCUGCGCUGCUGCUGCUGCUGUUACUGGGGUCGGCGAGCUCGGUCGGAGGGAACCGAUGUGUGGACGCGGCCGAAGCCUGCACGGCGGACGCGCGGUGCCAGCGUUUGCGCUCCGAGUAUGUGGCGCAGUGCCUGGGCCGGGCUGCGCAGGGGGGCUGUCCCCGCGCCCGCUGCCGCCGGGCCCUGCGCCGCUUCUUCGCCCGCGGGCCGCCCGCGCUCACCCACGCACUGCUCUUCUGCCCGUGCGCGGGCCCCGCGUGCGCCGAGCGUCGGCGCCAGACCUUCGUGCCCUCCUGCGCCUUUUCGGGGCCCGGCCCCGCGCCGCCCUCCUGCCUUGAGCCCUUAAACUUCUGCGAGCGCAGCCGGGUCUGCAGGUGCGCGCGGGCGGCGGCGGGGCCGUGGCGAGGGUGGGGACGGGGCCUCUCUCCGGCUCACCGCCCUCCCGCCGCGCAGGCCUCGCCUCCUGGCCUUUCAGGUCUCGUGCACCCCAGCGCCCAGCGCCCCCGACGGCUGCCUGCUGGACCAGGGCGCCCGCUGCCUGCGCGCCUACGCGGGCCUCGUGGGGUCCCCGCAGGCACCGCCGUCACCCCUAACUACGUGGACAACGUGAGCGCGCGCGUGGCGCCCUGGUGCGACUGCGGAGCCAGCGGGAACCGGCGUGAGGACUGCGAAGCCUUCCGGGGGCUCUUUACCAGGAACCGCUGCUUGGAUGGUGCCAUUCAGGCCUUUGCCAGCGGGUGGCCCCCAGUCCUGCUGGACCAGCUGAACCCCCAGGGAGACCCGGAGCACAGCCUCCUGCAGGUGUCCUCCACAGGCAGGGCCCUGGAGAGACGCUCCCUGCUCUCCAUACUUCCUGUCCUGGCUCUCCCGGCCCUGCUCUGAUUAGGACAGCGACCUCGGAUAGCACAGCCAGCUACUCCACCCUGCCUGCCUGGGCCGCCUCUGUGGCCUACUGGCCCCUUGAGAAGGGGCUGGCUUACCCCCCAAGCCGGCCCUGGUGCUUUCACUCCGCUGCCCUUUGUAGGUUUGGACACCCUGUGUGCCGUCCCCUGGGGCAAGGGAUGUAGGCUGGGGCCUGACUGUAAAGCCCCCGUCUCCCUGUCAGGAGGCAUCUUGGUUGUAAGUCCCUUUAUUCACAGACCUUGAGACCACUGGGGUCUCCCACAAGGUGGGGUCAGGAGAGGGUCACUUUUGUAGCUGAGACCUCUCUGGAGACCCAGAUCCCCUAGAGCAGGUCAGAGACCAUCCAGAAUCCCAGAAUUCUAGGAAAUUGUAUCAGCCUCCCAAGCAUAUAACCCCCUAAGGAAUCCAUCGGACAAGACCCCGUCUAACACUGCAUCCUCCCAACUGGGCAUUACCCACCAUUGUAGCCACCUGUGCGCCAUGACCAUGCUGGCAGAGUCUUUCCUGUUCCCCAUAUGCUGCUUGAGGGGCCCCACCCUGUGCCCUGCCUGGCAUUGGCCCUGUGGCCAUCUUCCCCCUGGUUUCCUGCAGCUGUAGGAAUAACAUACAGUGCUUAUUAAAUCUGUGUGCUGAGACUGAC